ACCCUGCAACCGGGCAGUCUCUUUCUGUUUACGGAGAGAAAGGGGAAAUGGAAAAGUCGGGGAGGCGGUGGCUGGCGUCCGCUGCGCCGCCCCUGGGCAGGCUCAGACGCCGUGAGUCAGGGGCAGAGCAGGGCGGUCUGAGCGUGCGGGCGACGCGGGUCUCACUCGUCCGCUCCGCUCUGGACUGCGCGCCACGCUCUGGGGUCCGGCGCCCUGGUUCCUGCUUCUGCCGCUGCCGCCGCCGGAUCCCAGUGGCCCGGCGUGCUCGGCUCCCACAGGCCUGCAGCCAGCAUCGCACCGAACCUUCGGGGGGCCGCGGCUGGAGCGCUCGGCCGGCGUGGGAGCGCCAAGGCCGCAGUAAAUUCGACAAGCAGAAACUGCAACUAAACGGCUCAGUAAAACCGAAGUCAAAUGUUCCUCCAUUAAUCUAAGAAGUUGCUCUCCUAACUCAGCAGACUCCAAGAACCUGAAUCACAAUCUCCCUCGAAGAUGUACAAGAUCUCAGGAGGGGAAGCUGCCCCCUCACUCUAGAUUUCACGGUGGUGAUAACAGCCAUGAAAGCAUUUCAUAGACUCUCCAGAAAGAGCAACAGUAAUGGAGUACAUGAGCACUGGAAGUGACAAUAAAGAAGAGAUUGAUUUAUUAAUUAAACAUUUAAAUGUGUCUGAUGUAAUAGACAUUAUGGAAAAUCUUUAUGCAAGUGAAGAGCCAGCAGUUUAUGAACCCAGUCUAAUGACCAUGUGUCAAGACAGUAAUCAAAACGAUGAGCGUUCUAAGUCUCUGCUGCUUAGUGGCCAAGAGGUACCAUGGUUGUCAUCAGUCAGAUAUGGAACUGUGGAGGAUUUGCUUGCUUUUGCAAACCAUAUAUCCAACACUGCAAAGCAUUUUUAUGGACAACGACCACAGGAAUCUGGAAUUUUAUUAAACAUGGUCAUCACUCCCCAAAAUGGACGUUACCAAAUAGAUUCCGAUGUUCUCCUGAUCCCCUGGAAGCUGACUUACAGGAAUAUUGGUUCUGAUUUUAUUCCUCGGGGCGCCUUUGGAAAGGUAUACUUGGCACAAGAUAUAAAGACGAAGAAAAGAAUGGCGUGUAAACUGAUCCCAGUAGAUCAAUUUAAGCCAUCUGAUGUGGAAAUCCAGGCUUGCUUCCGGCACGAGAACAUCGCAGAGCUGUAUGGCGCAGUCCUGUGGGGUGAAACUGUCCAUCUCUUUAUGGAAGCAGGCGAGGGAGGGUCUGUUCUGGAGAAACUGGAGAGCUGUGGACCAAUGAGAGAAUUUGAAAUUAUUUGGGUGACAAAGCAUGUUCUCAAGGGACUUGAUUUUCUACACUCAAAGAAAGUGAUCCAUCAUGAUAUUAAACCUAGCAACAUUGUUUUCAUGUCCACAAAAGCUGUUUUGGUGGAUUUUGGCCUAAGUGUUCAAAUGACCGAAGAUGUCUAUUUUCCUAAGGACCUCCGAGGAACAGAGAUUUACAUGAGCCCAGAGGUCAUCCUGUGCAGGGGCCAUUCAACCAAAGCAGACAUCUACAGCCUGGGGGCCACGCUCAUCCACAUGCAGACGGGCACCCCACCCUGGGUGAAGCGCUACCCUCGCUCAGCCUAUCCCUCCUACCUGUACAUAAUCCACAAGCAAGCACCUCCACUGGAAGACAUUGCAGAUGACUGCAGUCCAGGGAUGAGAGAGCUGAUAGAAGCUUCCCUGGAGAGAAACCCCAAUCACCGCCCAAGAGCCGCAGACCUACUAAAACAUGAGGCCCUGAACCCGCCCAGAGAGGAUCAGCCACGCUGUCAGAGUCUGGACUCUGCCCUCUUGGAGCGCAAGAGGCUGCUGAGUAGGAAGGAGCUGGAACUUCCUGAGAACAUUGCUGAUUCUUCGUGCACAGGAAGCACCGAGGAAUCUGAGAUGCUCAAGAGGCAACGCUCUCUCUACAUCGACCUCGGCGCUCUGGCUGGCUACUUCAAUCUUGUUCGGGGACCACCAACGCUUGAAUAUGGCUGAAGGAUGCCAUGUUUGCUCUAAAUUAAGACAGCAUUGAUCUCCUGGAGGCUGGUUCUGCUGCCUCUACACAGGGGCCCUGUACAGUGAAUGGUGCCAUUUUCGAAGGAGCAGUGUGACCUCCUGUGACCCGUGAAUGUGCCUCCAAGCGGCCCUGUGUGUUUGACAUGUGAAGCUAUUUGAUAUGCACCAGGUCUCAAGGUUCUCAUUUCUCAGGUGACGUGAUUCUAAGGCAGGAAUUUGAGAGUUCACAGAAGGAUCGUGUCUGCUGACUGUUUCAUUCACUGUGCACUUUGCUCAAAAUUUUAAAAAUACCAAUCACAAGGAUAAUAGAGUAGCCUAAAAUUACUAUUCUUGGUUCUUAUUUAAGUAUGGAAUAUUCAUUUUACUCAGAAUAGCUGUUUUGUGUAUAUUGGUGUAUAUUAUAUAACUCUUUGAGCCUUUAUUGGUAAAUUCUGGUAUACAUUGAAUUCAUUAUAAUUUGGGUGACUAGAACAACUUGAAGAUUGUAGCAAUAAGCUGGACUAGUGUCCUAAAAAUGGCUAACUGAUGAAUUAGAAGCCAUCUGACAGCAGGCCACUAGUGACAGUUUCUUUUGUGUUCCUAUGGAAACAUUUUAUACUGUACAUGCUAUGCUGAAGACAUUCAAAACGUGAUGUUUUGAAUGUGGAUAAAACUGUGUAAACCACAUAAUUUUUGUACAUCCCAAAGGAUGAGAAUGUGACCUUUAAGAAAAAUGAAAACUUUUGUAAAUUAUUGAUGAUUUUGUAAUUCUUAUGACUAAAUUUUCUUUUAAGCAUUUGUAUAUUAAAAUAGCAUACUGUGUAUGUUUUAUAUCAAAUGCCUUCAUGAAUCUUUCAUACAUAUAUAUAUUUGUAACAUUGUAAAGUAUGUGAGUAGUCUUAUGUAAAGUAUGUUUUUACAUUAUGCAAAUAAAACCCAAUACUUUUGUCCAAUGUGGUUGGUCAAAUCAACUGAAUAAAUUCAGUAUUUUGCCUUA